GGCAGAUGGAAGACUUGGGGGGGUCUCUGCCAGCUGGAAGUGCUUGGCUCCACUUAGCAGCUAAACUUAGCUUUUCAAUCGAUCGCUUUUGAAAGGGAAUUGUAUUUCUGUCCCCGUGCGGAUUCCAGACCAAAAUUGAAAAAAUGGUUGACCUCACCCAGGUAAUGGAUGAUGAAGUAUUCAUGGCUUUUGCAUCCUAUGCAACAAUUAUUCUUUCAAAAAUGAUGCUUAUGAGUACUGCAACUGCAUUCUAUAGAUUGACAAGAAAGGUUUUUGCCAAUCCAGAAGACUGUGUAGCAUUUGGCAAAGGAGAAAAUGCCAAGAAGUAUCUUCGAACAGAUGACAGAGUAGAACGUGUACGCAGGGCACAGGAGAUCUUAGGCCCAGAAAGGCAGAUUCAGAAGAACCUACAUGUAAAUGAGACUGGAGUGGAAAUGAGAAUGGCAGGAAAUGCAUGGAAACAGACUUGUAACUGUCUCAUGGCCUGGUCGUCCAAAUCCCAGAGGAUGGAGUGCAAUGGCAUGAUCUCAGCUCACCGCAACCUCUGCCUCCCGGAUUCAAGUGAUUCUCCUGCCUCAGCCUCUUGAGUAGCUGGGAUUACAGGUUGCUGCAGAAGUCAAGAGCUAACCAAGAAGACAAGGAAUGUAACAUAUUUAAUCAAAUAAGCACAUCAUCUCUAUUAUAAAGACAGUGGUUUGUUUAAUAACUAUCACUGACAAGAUUAUUUCAGAUUAUUUAAACACCAAGCAAACUAUCAGGUCAAGAUCAAGCAACUUUUCUUUAAGAUCAAGCUCAAAUUGAUCUGCCUUGGAAGACGAGGAUCACCAAGUGAUUAGGAAUAUAGGUUCCUCAACUCAAUCUGGACAAGAAAAGCAUCUGCCAGGAAGAACAGAGGGGGACUGUUAGAAAUUGUAACAGAAAAAAGCCCCCAAGAUGCAGACCACAGUAGGAAUUAAGCCUCGUAAAGCUCUCUGGCUACUGUCUCCGUCUAGCUUUCUGGGAAGUAUGUGUUGGAUUUUUUUGUGCAUGAAGUAUAAAUGCCACCGUUUUUGAAAGCCCACCCAUUCAUCCUGUACCUCCUUAUAAGAUUCAAAGCACAUUUGCAUAGCUUCUUAGCCAAGUAUGCAUGAAGAUAUCCCAGCCCAUUUUAUAAAUAUACAUGCAAGCUCGAGAACUUUGAUUUGUACCCAAAGUUUAAACUUAAACAUUUUUAAAAGACACUUUGUACAUACAAAUCCCACUGUUAUAAAUAGAAAUUAAUAUUUAACUUUUGGCUUUGAGGAUUAUGCUUAGCUCUUCUUGAAGCAAAACUAACAUUAGUGAGCUAGGAUUAAGGUUAGUGGGUUAGGUUAGUGGUGAGAAAUAUAAGCAUAAACAAACUCUCAUGUAACAUUUGUCUCAUCAAGAAUGUAAUUCACGAAAUUGUUUUAAAUAACAAUAUGUCCUUAAUGUAUCUUCUCUAAGUGCUGGAUUUAGAAACAUUUAUCAUAACUAGAGCAAAUAUAUUAUUUUACAUGUUUUGUAACUAUAAGAUAAUUAAAUAGGGCUUGGCUUGACUUUAAAAAGUGAAAAAAAUACAAGAAUAUCACCCCUCAGACCUAGAAUAGCGGACUUCAAGAGUAGAAAAUUAAUGGCCUUUGAAAAAUCCACAUCUUUGCAAUUUGUAUUACCUAAGAAUUAAAAAAAAAAAUCGGUAUCAUUGUGAUCAGGACAGUUUGAUGACAUCUUUGGUCAAGAUCUUACUCUCAUAAAUGCUGUGUUGGCAGUCCUAGCUCAUCAAUAUAGGCAUUUCCUUGAAUUUCACAUUGAAAUACUAUGAUGUAUAGAUAUUCCAUUUGCCAUAUUAAUAGACGAAUGUAGAUGCAUCACUUUAAAAUCAAACAUGCGACUAUAUCAUCCCCCUUAGAUUGGCAACAGAUCAUCACGUGACCAAAUCCAGAAGCCUAUUUUCAAAUUCAUAUUUCACAACUAUUACUUAAUCACACAGGGUCAUCAAUGGGGCCAAAUAAAAAGACAUCCAAAAAAACUUCCAGUAAAUAAAUGAAAAAUAAUCUCAUUCAAUUCAGCAGAUGAAUUCUAUAAUCCCAAAUGAAAUUGAUUUCACAACUGCCUCACUGAAUAAGCUUUACAAUGGUUUUCAAAUUGAAGUAUUAUCACUUUUCUAGGGGACAUUUAGAAAUGUAUACGGGGCAUUGUUUGUUGCAACAGUGAUAGGUGGUACCAUAGACCUACACAGUGACUACCCCUUAUUCUUGCCCCUCCUGCUCUCCCACACCCCAGCUGCACUAGUAUCUGUGAUGUCCUUCAAACAUAUGAGAAAAACUCCCACCUCAGGGCCUUUGUACUGGAUGUUCCUGAGCCCAGAAUGUCCUUCCCAUACGUGAUCAUGGCUAGCUCCUUCACUUUCAUCAGGUCAUUACUCAAGUCACCGUCUCAGUGAGGCUGUCUGCACCCCCUCCACACAAACCAAAAUUCUACAAACCUCUUGUACUGCUUCAUUUUCUCCUCAUUGUGUUUAUCAUCUCCUCAUGCCCUAUACUUAUUUUGUUGAUUACCUAUUUCCCCUAAGUAGAAUAUAAACUCUACAAGGGGAGCAGGUAUUUUUGUGUUUUAUUUAGUGCUUAUGUCAAGGCCUUUUACAGUACCUAGAAUAUACAGAAUGAUCACAUUUAUUGAAUGAAAAAAUGGGAAUGGGGAUGAUUGUUUUGCAAGAGGUAUCAAUUGUACAAGGAAAGAUAAGCAUUUUGCAAGGGGUGUCAAUUAUUGAUAACUUACUGAUAUCUGUGAUAAGAGAUGGAACAAUACAAAUAGCAUGAAAGUUACAAGCUAAGUCUGUCUUGCUCUGCACCCAAAAUAUAACCCGUGAAGCUCAAAGCUCAGCUUUCAUAAGAGGACCACUGGCUUAUGAAAUAAUUUUUAUGAAGUCCAGAUACUUUAUAACCUCCCUGCUUCAGAAUAUUUUCUAAUCUCUCCUGAUCAUACCUCUUGUCAUUCUCUAUAUUGGUUCCAUGGGACUUAAUUGGAGUGAAACUCUUUAUAUAUUCUACUUAGUUAUUUGACAAUAAUAGUGACUAUGUUUAUCAGGUGUAGAAAAUUUGAAAAAUAACUUGCUCUUAAGUUCUUUCCAAUUUUCCCAGACUGGAUAGCUUAUUCUUCACAAAAGAAAGUAUGUAUAACUUUGUACUUUAUAUAUUAUACAAAAUUAAUUAGAAAUGUAGUAUUUCACAUUCAUUAUUUAUAAGAACGAAGUAUUGGCACUCAAAUAUUUGUCAAGUGACUAAAUGGUUUCAUUGUAGAACUUUUAAAGAGAUAGCAAAGCAAGUAAUCAUAAACACAAACCCCAAUCCUGCCUCUCAGCAAGGGUUGCACCGUGAAAGAAGAGAUUCUUCUAGCUCAGGAACUUUCUAAUAUUUUUCCUAAUAAAUGGUCACAGAAAAUACUGGCUUAUAAAUUUGAAGGCAAUUACUUAUAAUUUCUUUGUAUCUCCCAAAGUGCAAAUGUUCCUCAGUGGAUAUUCACAUGCAAUAUUUAUAGACUCUAAAAUUACAUUCACAGUAUAAGUGAGCAUCUCACCUGUAAAAUGCAAAUAACCUGCUCAUGGAAACUAAUACUUGCAUGAAGUUACAACUGCUUUUUCCAUCCACUUCCCUUACUCCUACCCACCCAGGUAAAGGAACAGGUACUGAUCCACUCAUGUUACCAACUUUAUACAUAGAUAUUGGUAAGAAUAUAUUUUUAUUGAGCAGCUAAUAAACAAAAAAUAAGUGGUAUGCUUAAUGUUGUAAGGUAUUUUAAAAUGUAACAGUCUUGAUUCUUCUAUUUUUUGGUGAAAUGUGAGCAGUAUGUCAAAAAACACUAUCCUAGAGAUGGAAAAUUAAAAAACAUUAAAAAUAAUUACUAAAGAGAUUUCAAAAUCUUUUAAAAACAAAAAGAAUAAAAUAAUUUCAAAAACAGGUAAAUAAACAUCUCUGUUAGAACUGCUAAAAUAAAAACAUAACAUUGUUCUAAAAGUUUUAGAAACUAGGAGUAAAGUAAUGACAUCUAAAAUUAGCUUUUCCCUCUUGUUGCUUGUUGGGAUCCCACAGCAUAAAUGAGACAGGAAUUUAUUUUUUCUCUGUGGUAUCUGGAUUACUGUUAAACAUUAGGAUUAGCACAUUUUAUGAAGUUCCAUGCCUGCUUACUAGUCCUUGUCAUAUCUGAUAUUUAUGUUUACUAAAAUUGAUUUUCUCUUUUUAUUAAUAGCUUGGGUUUAAUGUGGACGAUGCUUCACUGCAUUAGUGAUAACAAUUUUACUUAAAUAUUGCUUUGGUGUGCUCUUCUGCAAAUACUCUUUCAAUUCCUAAGAGUCUUUUAUUUUCCCAGUAGCCCAGUUGGAGAGUUUUAAUAUUAAAUUGAAUCAUAACAACA